CACAGCCAGUGUACUGGAUGCCUGAUUAAGCGUCAUGGGGUCUUUCAUCCAGACUGCGUUUUCAUUAUUCGCUGAAACAUACAGGUUUUAAUUUUUACGAGGCUAAGGCCACGGCCGCCUCACCUCGGUUUUUGCCGCCACCUAGAGGAACUAUGUGCGCCCCAACGGUUGCCCGGAUGUAGGCGUAGGGUGGAGCCGUAAGAGAUUGACUAGCCAGUUGAUUUGGUUGGCGCAGGCUCAGAAACGCCGUGACGCCGCCCUUCCCCCCAACACGUGAUGAAAGUCGGGGUGACGAAGGGCCGGCUUUGCGCAGGUGCACAGUACUCGCUAUGGCCCAUUCGUCACGUGACGAGGGCGGGACUGUGGCACUGUGGAGGGGCGCCUAGUAGGCAGGCGCUCUCAGCUCUCUCCCCGGUUCCCACUGAAGGAUGGUCCCCGGCUGCAGGCCUGGCUGCAGCACAUGGGCUGUGAGCACUGGGUGCCCAGCUGCCACCAGCACUUGUGCAGCGAGCACUUCACACCCUCCUGCUUCCAGUGGCGCUGGGGUGUGCGCUACCUGCGGCCUGAUGCAGUGCCCUCCAUCUUCUCCCGGGGACCACCUGCCAAGAGUCAGCGGAGGACCCGAAGCACCCAGAAGCCAGUCUCGCCGCCGCCUCCCCUACAGAAGAAUACACCCCUGCCCCAGAGCCCUGCCAUCCCAGUCUCUGGCCCAGUGCGCCUAGUGGUGCUGGGCCCCACAUCGGGGAGCCCCAAGACUGUGGCCACCAUGCUCCUGACCCCCCUGGCCCCUGCGCCAACUCCUGAGCGGUCACAACCUGAAGUCCCUGCCCAACAGGCCCAGACCGGGCUGGGCCCAGUGCUGGGAGCACUGCAACGCCGGGUGCGGAGGCUGCAACGGUGCCAGGAGCGGCACCAGGCGCAGCUGCAGGCCCUGGAACGGCUGGCACAGCAGCUACACGGGGAGAGCCUGCUGGCACGGGCACGCCGGGGUCUGCAGCGCCUGACAACAGCCCAGACCCUUGGACCUGAGGAAUCCCAAACCUUCACCAUCAUCUGUGGAGGGCCUGACAUAGCCAUGGUCCUUGCCCAGGACCCUGCACCUGCCACAGUGGAUGCCAAGCCGGAGCUCCUGGACACUCGGAUCCCCAGUGCAUAAGGAUCAAGACAGACAAUGUCGAGGGACAAAAGAUAGAAGAUGGAGGAGGAAAGACAUUAUACGUGGGCUUGGCCCAGCCCCACCGCCCACGCCUGGGUAGUAGCAGUGCCUCCCUCAAGGGCCUGGGUUCUACCACCCCACUCCUAGGGAUCUCUUGAACCUUAGGGGUGACCUGGGCCCAAGUCUCUCAUCAGCCCCCAAUCCCCUGGGUACCAGGCUUCUGCCACCCCCGGCUCAGAUCUUUGCAAAUCAGUACGACAGCCUCAGAGCAGAGCAAGGGUUGUUUGGGAGAAUCAUACCUGGUUCUAAGGAGUCCCACGCUUUUUGCCAAGCCUGGUACUGAGUUCAUGAUACCAUGGUGGACACAGCUGAGAAAAUCCCUGCCCUCAUGGUGCUCAUUCUACUUGAGUAGACGAUGAACUAGUAAACAAAUAAACAAGAACACUGCAGACAUG